GCAUUUCCGGAGCGCCAGGGAAGAGGGAAGUCGUGGUGGUCGCGAGGGAGCCGGAAAGAUGGUGGUUACCAGAUCUGCACGGGCUAAGGCCAGCAUCCAAGCCGCGUCGGCUGAAAGUUCCGGGCAAAAGAGUUUUGCUGCUAAUGGGAUUCAAGCGCAUCCAGAAAGUAGUACUGGAUCUGAUGCCCGAACUACUGCUGAAUCACAGACCACUGGGAAGCAAAGUUUAAUCCCUAGAACUCCUAAAGCUAGAAAGAGGAAGAGCAGAACUACAGGCUCACUACCAAAGGGGACUGAACCAUCUACGGAUGGAGAAACCUCUGAGGCAGAGUCAAAUUAUUCUGUGUCUGAGCACCAUGAUACCAUUUUAAGGGUAACUAGGAGAAGGCAGAUCUUAAUUGCAUGCUCCCCAGUGUCCAGUGUUAGGAAAAAGCCGAAAGUAACUCCAACAAAGGAGUCUUACACUGAAGAAAUAGUGUCUGAAGCAGAAUCUCAUGUUUCAGGUAUUUCUAGAAUUGUGCUUCCUACAGAAAAAACUACAGGAGCCAGAAGAAGUAAGGCUAAAUCUCUGACAGAUCCAAGCCAAGAAUCUCAUACAGAAGCUAUAUCUGAUGCUGAGACAUCAAGCUCAGACAUUUCAUUCUCUGGAAUUGCAACUAGAAGAACCAGGAGUAUGCAGAGGAAAUUAAAGGCACAAACUGAAAAGAAAGAUAGUAAGAUUGUACCAGGAAAUGAGAAACAGAUCGUGGGUACACCUGUGAAUUCAGAGGAUUCAGAUACCAGACAAACUUCCCAUUUACAAGCAAGAUCUCUUUCUGAGAUAAAUAAGCCAAAUUUCUAUAAUAAUGACUUUGAUGAUGAUUUCUCCCACAGAAGUUCAGAAAAUAUAUUAACAGUGCACGAACAGGCCAAUGUUGAAUCUCUUAAAGAAACAAAACAGAAUUGUAAGGAUUUGGAUGAAGAUGCCAAUGGAAUAACAGAUGAGGGGAAAGAAAUUAAUGAGAAAAGUUCUCAGCUGAAGAAUCUUUCUGAACUUCAGGACACUAGCCUUCAACAGUUAGUUUCUCAGAGACAUUCAACCCCCCAAAAUAAAAAUGCUGUAUCAGUGCACUCUAAUCUGAACUCUGAGGCUGUAAUGAAAUCAUUAACUCAAACAUUUGCAACUGUGGAAGUAGGCAGAUGGAAUAACAACAAAAAGAGCCCCAUAAAAGCAAGUGACUUGACAAAGUUUGGUGAUUGUGGUGGUAGUGAUGAUGAAGAAGAGUCCACAGUUAUAAGUGUCAGUGAAGACAUGAACAGUGAAGGGAAUGUAGAUUUUGAAUGUGAUACCAAACUAUACACGUCUGCGCCCAACACAUCUCAGGGUAAAGAUAAUUCUGUCUUACUAGUUCUCAGCAGUGAUGAAAGCCAACAGUCUGAAAACAGUGAGAAUGAAGAGGAUACUUUAUGUUUUGUUGAAAAUAGUGGCCAAAGGGAGUCAUUAAGUGGAGACACAGGAAGUCUGUCAUGUGACAAUGCAUUGUUUGUAAUUGACACAACUCCUGGAAUGAGUGCUGAUAAAAAUUUUUACUUGGAAGAGGAAGACAAGGCAAGUGAGGUUGCCAUUGAGGAAGAAAAAGAAGAGGAAGAGGAUGAAAAAAGUGAAGAAGAUUCAUCAGACCAUGACGAAAAUGAAGAUGAGUUUAGUGAUGAAGAAGACUUCCUAAAUAGCACAAAGGCUAAACUUCUGAAGUUGACAAGCAGCAGCAUAGACCCUGGUCUGAGUAUCAAGCAGUUGGGUGGUUUGUAUAUUAAUUUUAAUGCAGAUAAACUACAGUCUAACAAGAGAACCCUAACACAGAUCAAGGAGAAAAAGAAAAAUGAGCUUCUGCAGAAAGCCGUCAUUACACCUGAUUUUGAAAAAAACCACUGUGUUCCACCAUAUAGUGAAUCAAAGUAUCAACUUCAGAAAAAACGCAGAAAAGAACGACAAAAAACAGCAGGGGAUGGCUGGUUUGGUAUGAAAGCUCCAGAAAUGACAAAUGAACUGAAAAAUGAUCUCAAAGCACUGAAGAUGAGAGCCAGCAUGGACCCGAAAAGAUUUUACAAGAAAAAUGAUAGAGAUGGCUUCCCCAAGUACUUCCAGAUUGGAACCAUUGUUGACAAUCCAGCUGAUUUCUACCAUUCACGAAUUCCCAAGAAGCAAAGGAAAAGAACUAUUGUGGAAGAACUGCUGGCUGAUUCUGAAUUCAGAAGAUACAACCGAAGGAAGUACUCAGAGAUCAUGGCUGAAAAAGCAGCAAAUGCAGCAGGAAAAAAGUUCCGAAAGAAGAAGAAAUUUCGCAAUUAAGAUUUACCAAGCAAACUGCAACAUUUUACAUUGCUCCUUUAUUUACUUAUUAAAGACGUUUGGAAAACUAACACCAUCAUCUAAAUUAAUUUACCAUAGACUGGCCCUGUUCAUACAGGAAUUUGUAUUUGGAAAAAGUUGAUUUGAGAAUCGAUUACAUGCCCUUAGAAAAUAGGGGUGUCUAAAAGACCCACCCUGGUGUAGACUCUUUAUGGGAAAAAAGGAAAAAAAAUCUCAACCAUUUUAAGAUAACUGAUGGUUUGUAAAGUUUUCAAUGCUUAGUUAUUUAAAGAAAAUUUAAUUAAAAGAUAGGAAGUAUAAAGUUUGCUAACAUGUUCAAAGAACUUUAAAAAAUGAUCAAAGAUAUAUAAACAUUAUUGUAAUUAAUAGGUAGUUUUAUGUGUGUAUGUGUGUGUGUGUCUGUGUAGGGGACGGGAGAUGGUAGAGAGGCAAUGCCCUAUAGUUAGCUAUAAAAUUCAGAUCCAGAAAGUUGGGAUACAAAGAUAUGAAGAAUAUGACCUAGAAAGCUUGGGCAGAGGAGCUGUUUUCCUUGCUUGGCAACUGAAACAGGGAGGAAUAAUUGGUUUUUAUCUAGAUUUAAGUGUUGUGGUCCAAGUAAAACAGGAUUAAACUAUAAUUUAAGUUGGCCAGGGUUUCUUCGAAGUUAACCCAGCUUACCUCUUCUCCAGUGGUACAGUAUGCACCCUGGCUAAGCUGGUUUCUGGCACCCAAGGAGUGUUGGUCAUUUCUGUUGAUACUUGGUGAGUUGUAGCUUCCUUUAUGUUACUAUUCACUUUACCUCUAUUUUUCCAGCAUACUGCUUCCUUGAGAUAUCAGCAAAUAUGAAAUCUUUUUUUUUUUUAAUAAUAGUUUUGGGGUACAUGUGUAGAACAUGCAGGUUACAUAGGUAUACACGUGCCAUGGUGGUUUGCUGCACCCAUCAACCUAUCUACAUUAGGUAUUUCUCCUAGUGCUAUCCCUCCCCUAGUCCCCCACCCACAACAGGCCCCAGUGUGUGAUGUUCCCCUCCCUGUGUCCAUGUGUUCUCAUUGUUUACCUCCCACUUACGAGUAAGAACAUGCAGUGUUUGGUUUUCUGUUCUUGUGUUAGUUUUCUGUUCUUGCUGAGAUGAUUUCCAGCUUCAGCCAUGUCCCUGCAAAGGACAUGAACUCAUGCUUUUUUAUGGCCACAUAGUAUUCCAUGGUGUAUAUGUGCCACAUUUUCUUUAUCCAGUCUAUCAUUCAUGGGCAUUUGGGUUGGUUCCAAGUCUUUUCUAUUGUGAACAGUGCCACAGUAAACAUACUUGUGUAUGUGUCUUUAUAGUAGAAUGAUUUAUAAUCCUUUGGGUAUAUACCCAGUAAUGGGAUUGCUGGGUCAAAUGGUAUUUCUGGUCCUAGAUCCUUGCGGAAUCACCACACUGUCUUCCACAAUGGUUGAACUAGUUUACACUCCCACCAACAGUGUAAAAGUGUUCCUAGUUCUCCAUAUCCUCUCCAGCAUCUGUUGUUUCCUGACUUUUUAAUGAUUGCCAUUCUAACUGGCAAUGAGAUGGUAUCUCAUUGUGGUUUUGAUUUGCAUUUCUCUAAUGAGCAGUGAUAAUGAGCGUUUUUUCAUGUUUGUUGGCUGCAUAAAUGUCUUCUUUUGAGAAGUGUCUGUUCAUAUCCUUCACCCACUUUUUGAUGGGGUUUUUUCUUGUAAAUUUGUUUAAGUUCUUUGUAGAUUCUGGAUAUUAGCCCUUUGUCAGAUGGAUAGAUUACAGAAAUUUUCUCCCAUUCUGUAGAUUGCCUGUGCACUCUGAUAAUAGUUUCUUUUGCUGUGCAGAAACUCUUUAGUUUAAUUAGAUCCCACUUGUCAAUUUUGCCUUUUGUUGCCAUUGCUUUUGGUGUUUUAGUCAUGCAGUCUGCCCAUACCUAUGUCCAAAAUCUCAUAUUUACUGCUUGGAGUCAAAAGCUAGUAAUAGCAGAACUGACAAUAACAUUCAUAGUUGGAGUUAGGGAAGCAUCUAUGUCUGUUCUCUUUUAUUUUAAAAAAAAACUACUUUUGUUUCUGGAAUACUAUGUUUUGCCUUCUACUGGAUAAAAUAAGGACCCAGUAUGAGAGAAUUGUAUCCUUUAGUGCUUCUGGCCUUCUACAAAUACCUGGAUAUUUAAAUAAUGGAUGAAGUUAUGUUUUGCUUUUUAAUAAGCAAGUCUUUUGAGAAACAGGUUUUACUGACUUUGGCCUGUGUCACUAAACUCAGUUCACCUACUGGAACUUUUUUUUUUUUUUUUGAGACGUCUCACUCCAUCACCCAGGUUGGAGUGCAGUGGUGCCAUCUCAGCUCACUGCAACCUCCGCCUCCCAAGUUCAAGCGAUUAUCAUACCUCAGCCUGCCAAGUAGCUGGGACUACUGGGCAUGCCAUUAUGCCCAGCUAACUUUUGUAUUUUUAGUAGAGAUGGGGUUUUGCCAUCCUUACCUCAAGUGAUCCACCCGCCUCGGCCUCCCAAAGUGCUGGGAUUACAGGUGUGAGCCACCAUGCCCAGCCAACUGGAACUAUUUGAAGGCUUUAUACCAGAAAAGUAUAAAGAAUCCAAAGGGCUGCCACAGUCAGGUGUGCUGGUGAAAGAGACCUUCAAGAUACCCCUGAGAAGAUCUUGAAAGAUUUCGAAAAGAAUGCUGUAUUUAUACACCAUCUGGCUCCAAGAUGCUUUUUUUUUUUUUUUUUUUGAGAGACGGACUCUCGCUCUGUCGCCCAGGCUGGAGUGUAGUGGCAUGAUCUUGGUUCACUGCAACCUCCGCCUCCCGGGUUCAAGCAAUUCUGCCUCAGCCUCCCAAGUACCUGGGAUUAACAGGCACCCACCACCACACCCGGCUAAUUUUUGUAUUUUUAGUAGAGACGGGGUUUCACCAUGUUGGCCAGGCUGGUCUUGAACUUCUGACCUCAGGUGAUCCACCGGCCUCAGCCUCCCAAAGUGCUGGGAUUACAGGCAGGAGCCACCACGUCUGGCCCAAAAUGUUCUUAAAACAAAGUAGAUGCUGUAAGACUACAGUUGAUAAAGUUGGGCUCUGGGCUAGGUUCUUAGCAUCCAACACAAUCAGUUCUGUGUUCAGUGUUCUGCUGUAUGAUAAACCAACUGCUCUAGAGAAACACCAAUAUUCCUCUUCUGAAACCUGGGAAAAUGUCUUUUUUGGGUCCCAUAACUAGAUGUCACAAAAGGAGUGGGGAGUGGGGAGGCUAUAUAAAAAAGUUCAACAAAACCUUAGUAACUGGUAUACAUUAAUAGGAUCCCAUUCUUAGAAACAGCAAGUUAAAGAAAAUACCAUAAUGGGAAAAAAAAGUUAACAUUUCUGAGAGAUGUACCAGGUAUUCAGUCUCUCAGGCAGUGACAACUUGUUCAGAAUAAUUACCUACAAUAGAUCCCAAACCAUUGAAAAAUGCCUAAUUGUUUACUUAAUGGAAUUUGUACUUACUAUUUAAUUAGAUGAAUAUCUUUAUUGAAAGUUUUCAGUAAGGGUUGCAACAAAAAGGGCUUUCUAAUUAACCAAUUCCCCAAGCAUCUGUCUAAUUAAAAUGUAAAGUGCAAUUA